GUUGGUGAAGAUCUUAACACCACGCCUUGAGCAAGUCGCAAGAGCGGGAGGACACAGACCAGGAACCGAGAAGGGACAAGCACAUGGAAGCCAGCCCAGCAUCCGGGCCCAGACACUUGAUGGAUCCACACAUAUUCACUUCCAACUUUAACAAUGGCAUUGGAAGGCAUAAGACCUACCUGUGCUACGAAGUGGAGCGCCUGGACAAUGGCACCUCGGUCAAGAUGGACCAGCACAGGGGCUUUCUACACAACCAGGCUAAGAAUCUUCUCUGUGGCUUUUACGGCCGCCAUGCGGAGCUGCGCUUCUUGGACCUGGUUCCUUCUUUGCAGUUGGACCCGGCCCAGAUCUACAGGGUCACUUGGUUCAUCUCCUGGAGCCCCUGCUUCUCCUGGGGCUGUGCCGGGGAAGUGCGUGCGUUCCUUCAGGAGAACACACACGUGAGACUGCGUAUCUUCGCUGCCCGCAUCUAUGAUUACGACCCCCUAUAUAAGGAGGCACUGCAAAUGCUGCGGGAUGCUGGGGCCCAAGUCUCCAUCAUGACCUACGAUGAAUUUAAGCACUGCUGGGACACCUUUGUGGACCACCAGGGAUGUCCCUUCCAGCCCUGGGAUGGACUAGAUGAGCACAGCCAAGCCCUGAGUGGGAGGCUGCGGGCCAUUCUCCAGAAUCAGGGAAACUGAAGGAUGGGCCUCAGUCUCUAAGGAAGGCAGAGACCUGGGUUGAGCAGCAGAAUAAAAGAUCUUCUUCCAAGAAAUGCAAACAGACCGUUCACCACCAUCUCCAGCUGCUCACAGACGCCAGCAAAGCAGUAUGCUCCCGAUCAAGUAGAUUUUUAAAAAAUCAGAGUGGGCCGGGCGCGGUGGCUCACGCCUGUAAUCCCAGCACUUUGGAGGCCAAGGCGGGUGGAUCACGAGGUCAGGAGAUCGAGACCAUCCUGGCUAACACGGUGAAACCCUGUCUCUACUAAAAAUACAAAAAAUUAGCCAGGCGUGGUGGCGGGCGCCUGUAGUCCCAGCUACUCUGGAGGCUGAGGCAGGAGAGUAGCGUGAACCCGGGAGGCAGAGCUUGCGGUGAGCCGAGAUUGCGCUACUGCACUCCAGCCUGGGCGACAGUACCAGACUCCAUCUCAAAAAAAAAAAAACCAGACUGAAUUAAUUUUAACUGAAAAUUUCUCUUAUGUUCCAAGUACACAAUAGUAAGAUUAUGCUCAAUAUUCUCAGAAUAAUUUUCAAUGUAUUAAUGAAAUGAAAUGAUAAUUUGGCUUCAUAUCUAGACUAACACAAAAUUAAGAAUCUUCCAUAAUUGCUUUUGCUCAGUAACUGUGUCAUGAAUUGCAAGAGUUUCCACAAACACUA